AGCCGAAGCGGCUGGAGCGGGCGGCAAGGCGAGGCGAAAGCUGCACAGGGCCCUACGCGGCCGCCUCAGCAUGUCGGACUUCGACGAGUUCGAGCGGCAGCUCAACGAGAAUAAACAAGCCUCUAGCCCUGCCCCUCUCAGGGACGACCCUGGGGUCAGGCCCCUCAGCCCUCGAGGGGGACCAGGAGCCAGCCUCCUCUGUCUUCUCUGGCUCCCCAGCUCCUCCUGAGCAUCCUCAGAGCGGGACAAGGAGAACCGGCAUCGGAAGCGCAGCCACAGCCGCUCUCGGAGCCGGGACCGCAAACGCCGGAGCCGGAGCCGCGACCGGCGCAACCGGGACCAGCGGAGCGCCUCCCGGGACAGGCGACGACGCAGCAAACCUUUGACCAGAGGCGCUAAAGAGGAGCACGGUGGACUGAUUCGUUCCCCCCGCCACGAGAAGAAGAAGAAGGUCCGUAAAUACUGGGACGUGCCACCCCCAGGCUUUGAGCACAUCACCCCAAUGCAGUACAAGGCCAUGCAAGCUGCGGGUCAGAUUCCAGCCACUGCUCUUCUCCCCACCAUGACCCCUGACGGUCUGGCUGUGACCCCAACGCCGGUGCCCGUGGUCGGGAGCCAGAUGACCAGACAAGCCCGGCGCCUCUACGUGGGCAACAUCCCCUUUGGCAUCACUGAGGAGGCCAUGAUGGAUUUCUUCAACGCCCAGAUGCGCCUGGGGGGGCUGACCCAGGCCCCUGGCAACCCAGUGUUGGCUGUGCAGAUUAACCAGGACAAGAAUUUUGCCUUUUUGGAGUUCCGCUCAGUGGACGAGACUACCCAGGCUAUGGCCUUUGAUGGCAUCAUCUUCCAGGGCCAGUCACUAAAGAUCCGCAGGCCUCACGACUACCAGCCGCUUCCUGGCAUGUCAGAGAACCCCUCCGUCUAUGUGCCUGGGGUUGUGUCCACUGUGGUCCCCGACUCUGCCCACAAGCUGUUCAUCGGGGGCUUACCCAACUACCUGAACGAUGACCAGGUCAAAGAGCUGCUGACAUCCUUUGGGCCCCUCAAGGCCUUCAACCUGGUCAAGGACAGUGCCACGGGGCUCUCCAAGGGCUACGCCUUCUGUGAGUACGUGGACAUCAACGUCACGGAUCAGGCCAUUGCGGGGCUGAACGGCAUGCAGCUGGGGGAUAAGAAGCUGCUGGUCCAGAGGGCGAGUGUGGGAGCCAAGAAUGCCACGCUGGUGAGCCCCCCGAGCACCAUCAAUCAGACGCCUGUGACCCUGCAAGUGCCGGGCUUGAUGAGCUCCCAGGUGCAGAUGGGCGGCCACCCGACUGAGGUCCUGUGCCUCAUGAACAUGGUGCUGCCUGAGGAGCUGCUGGACGACGAGGAGUAUGAGGAGAUCGUGGAGGACGUGCGGGACGAGUGCAGCAAGUACGGGCUUGUCAAGUCCAUCGAGAUCCCCCGGCCUGUGGACGGCGUCGAGGUGCCCGGCUGCGGAAAGAUCUUUGUGGAGUUCACCUCUGUGUUUGACUGCCAGAAAGCCAUGCAGGGCCUGACGGGCCGCAAGUUCGCCAACAGAGUGGUUGUCACAAAAUACUGUGACCCCGACUCUUAUCACCGCCGGGACUUCUGGUAGAGGCGGCUGGGGGAGGGUGGGGGCAGGGCUGGCUGGGGGCUUCUCCCCACUCCCGCCCCCCCCUUAUCCCCCUCUGAAGACGAUGGGCAGAGGAGUGACAGCCGCAGACACACGACAGCCGGCAGCAACUGGAAUGGCAGCAAUUAAGGGUGGGGGGCGGGGGUUGGGGGGUUGGGGGGUUAGGGCAGGGAGGGGACUGGGGAAGUGCGCACACAGCCCACACAGACAACACGCACCCACACAGACACAGAGGGAAGGGGUUGGGAUGGGGACAGGGUGCACAGCAGGGCGGGGUAGGACCCCAGCCCCUCCCAAAACAGCCUCUCCUUCUCCCAUAGACCCCUUUCUUCUCCCCUUCCCCACGGUAGGAACAUAGCGUGUUUAUAUUUUAUGGCCAAACUAUUUUGAAUUUUGUUGUCCGGCCCUCAGUGCCCUGCCCUCUCCCUUACCAGGACCACAGCUCUGUUCCUUCGGCCUCUGGUCCUCUCUGGUCCCCUCCUGGGUUUCUUACGUAGUUGAUUUUUCCUCUUUAGUCUCCCCCGACCUGCGCCCAGCCCCGUGGCCCCUGCCCCUCUCCUACUCUCUGUGGCAGUUUCAUAUUUGCUAAGACGAAUUUGCUCAUUAAACAUUUUGUUGUAUUUUACUUUA